ACUUUUACAUUUUUGUCUUCAUUGCUUAACAUCGUUUUUAAGAAUUCAAAAUGUCCGGACGCGGCAAGCAAGGCGGAAAGGCCCGAGCUAAGGCUAAGACCCGCUCUUCGCGGGCCGGACUCCAGUUCCCUGUGGGCCGCGUACACCGCUUGCUCCGCAAGGGCAACUACUCCGAGCGAGUCGGGGCCGGCGCGCCAGUGUAUCUGGCGGCGGUGUUGGAGUACCUGACCGCCGAGAUCCUGGAGCUGGCGGGCAACGCCGCCCGCGACAACAAGAAGACCCGCAUCAUCCCCCGACACCUGCAGCUGGCCAUCCGCAACGACGAGGAGCUAAACAAGUUGCUGGGUAAAGUCACAAUUGCUCAGGGCGGUGUUCUGCCCAACAUCCAGGCUGUACUGCUCCCCAAGAAGACUGAGAGUCACCACAAGGCCAAGGCAGGGUUUAGAAGUUCGCAAUGGCUCGUACCAAGCAGACUGCUCGCAAGUCCACGGGUGGGAAAGCGCCACGCAAGCAGCUGGCCACCAAGGCUGCUCGAAAGAGCGCUCCAGCCACCGGCGGCGUGAAGAAGCCCCACCGUUACCGGCCCGGCACGGUGGCUCUGCGCGAGAUCCGCCGCUACCAGAAGUCGACCGAGCUGCUGAUUCGCAAACUGCCAUUCCAGCGUCUAGUCCGUGAGAUCGCGCAGGACUUCAAGACUGAUCUGCGUUUUCAGAGCUCGGCGGUGAUGGCGCUGCAGGAGGCCUGCGAGGCCUACCUGGUGGGGCUGUUUGAGGACACCAACCUAUGCGCCAUUCACGCCAAGCGAGUGACUAUCAUGCCCAAGGACAUCCAGCUUGCUCGCCGCAUUCGUGGGGAGAGGGCGUAAAUUGUCUUGUGAAUGUGUGCUAACCAAAACCCAAAGGCUCUUUUCAGAGCCAACCA